GGUUUGGGAGGCCCAGGCGGCGGAGCCUCCGGGACGGCGAGCGGCGGGCGGCGGAGGAGGAGACGGCAGGUCGGACUGACCAAAUAUGGAAGUGUGCAAGUCUUGAACACAUUAGUUUAUACAAUGUGGCCUGAAAGUUUCCCUCCUCUUUCCAAAUCAACCAUAAUAUUCUGAGGCAUUAAAAAAUAUUUAAUCAUUCAUGUGUUGAGACUCAUUCUUGAGUUAUGGAUGACAAGGCUUCUGUUGGAAAAAUCAGUGUCUCUUCAGACUCAGUAUCUACUCUUAAUAGUGAAGAUUUUGUCUUGGUUUCCAGGCAAGGAGAUGAGACACCAUCUACAAAUAAUGGAAGUGAUGAUGAGAAAACAGGACUCAAGAUUGUAGGGAAUGGAAGUGAACAGCAGCUGCAAAAAGAGCUAGCAGAUGUACUGAUGGAUCCUCCAAUGGACGACCAGCCAGGGGAAAAGGAGCUUGUGAAAAGGUCACAACUGGAUGGUGAAGGAGAUGGGCCUCUUUCUAAUCAGCUCUCCGCUUCAUCCACCAUUAACCCUGUGCCAUUAGUAGGGCUCCAAAAACCAGAGAUGAGCCUACCAGUGAAACCUGGACAAGGAGAUUCUGAAGCUUCAAGUCCUUUCACACCAGUGGCCGAUGAGGACAGCGUAGUUUUCAGUAAACUGACUUACUUAGGCUGUGCCUCGGUAAAUGCUCCCAGGAGUGAAGUGGAAGCCUUAAGGAUGAUGUCCAUCUUAAGAAGCCAGUGUCAGAUUUCACUAGAUGUUACCCUUUCAGUGCCGAAUGUGUCUGAAGGAAUUGUGAGACUCUUAGAUCCUCAGACAAACACUGAAAUAGCAAACUACCCUAUCUACAAAAUCCUCUUCUGUGUCAGAGGGCAUGAUGGAACUCCUGAGAGUGACUGUUUUGCUUUCACUGAAAGUCAUUACAAUGCAGAGCUCUUCAGAAUACACGUCUUCCGGUGUGAAAUACAAGAAGCUGUAAGCCGGAUACUUUACAGUUUUGCCACUGCCUUCCGCCGUUCUGCCAAGCAGACCCCACUUUCAGCCACUGCUGCACCCCAGACUCCUGACAGUGACAUCUUUACCUUCUCUGUGUCUUUAGAAAUAAAAGAAGAUGAUGGUAAAGGUUAUUUUAGUGCAGUUCCCAAAGAUAAGGACAGACAGUGCUUUAAACUACGCCAAGGAAUUGAUAAGAAGAUUGUCAUCUAUGUGCAGCAAACAACUAAUAAAGAACUUGCCAUUGAAAGGUGUUUUGGUCUUCUCCUUAGUCCAGGAAAAGAUGUACGAAAUAGUGACAUGCACUUAUUAGAUUUGGAAUCUAUGGGCAAAAGUUCAGAUGGAAAGUCGUAUGUUAUUACGGGGAGCUGGAAUCCAAAAUCCCCACAUUUUCAAGUUGUAAAUGAAGAAACUCCUAAAGAUAAAGUCCUGUUUAUGACCACAGCUGUAGAUUUGGUAAUAACAGAAGUACAGGAGCCUGUUCGAUUUCUCCUGGAGACAAAAGUCCGCGUUUGCUCACCUAAUGAAAGAUUAUUCUGGCCCUUCAGCAAACGUAGUACUACUGAAAAUUUCUUUUUGAAACUAAAACAGAUAAAGCAAAGGGAGAGAAAGAAUAAUACUGACACUUUAUAUGAAGUUGUAUGCUUGGAAAGUGAAUCAGAAAGAGAGAGGAGGAAAACUACAGCCAGUCCUUCAGUUCGCCUGCCACAGUCUGGAUCGCAAAGUUCAGUGAUACCUUCUCCUCCAGAAGAUGAUGAAGAGGAAGAUAAUGAUGAACCUCUCCUGAGUGGAUCUGGUGAUGUAUCCAAAGAAUGUGCAGAAAAAAUUCUUGAAACAUGGGGAGAACUGUUGUCAAAAUGGCAUCUCAACUUGAAUGUGAGACCGAAGCAGUUGUCAUCCUUAGUAAGAAACGGUGUCCCUGAAGCUCUUCGAGGAGAAGUCUGGCAGCUGCUAGCAGGCUGUCAUAACAAUGACCACCUGGUAGAGAAAUACCGCAUUCUUAUCACAAAGCUCAUUCCUCUAAAGUGAAAAAAAUCUCAUUUGUAUGGUGUUCCCCUUCUGAAGUUCAUGCAUUCCUCAAAGUUUUGCAAGCAAAACAAGAAAAACUAUUUCUUCUACAAGCAUAUCAGGAUUUAAAGUAAUUUUCUGCAAUGUUAGGCAAUGUUUUGUGCCUUUGUGUUCAUGUUUUCGGUUUUAGUUUUAAUUUUCUCAAAUUCUUGAAGUGUUUAUCUUCAGGAAGCAGUUUCUCCAAUAGUAUGCAAAUCCCAAACCUGGGUCGUGAAUGUAUUGCUCAGAAUCUUCAAGAAUAUAGGAGAUUUUUCAAUGUGACAGAAGGUAAAACUUUGUCUUAAAAAAGAAAAAAAGUUAAAACCUUAUAAAUUAUGAAUGAUAUCUCUCUGUAAAGCUGUUAUUUAAAAAAAAAAAAAAAACCUUAUAAGGGAAGAGCAGGCUUUUUUUUUUUUUUUUUUUGAAAUAGAGUCUUGCCCAGGCUGGAGUGCAGUGGCAUGAUCUAGGCUCACCGCAACCUCUGCCUCCCGGCUUUAAGCAAUUGUUGUGCCUCCAUCUCCCAAGAAGCUGGGAUUACAGGUGCGCACCACCAUGCCUAAUUUUUGUAAUUUUAGUAGAGAGUAGGGUUUCUCCAUUUUGGCCAGACUGGUCUUGAAUUCCUGGCCUCAAGCAAUCCAACUGUCUUGGCCUCCCAAAGUGCUGGAAUUACAGGUGUGAGCUGCCUCACCUGGCCUGGAAAAACAGCAUUCAAACAUGAGAUAGGACCUUCACCAGAAAAUGACUUUUAUGUCUUCAGAAUAUUAAUGUUCUUUCCCAUCAUCCUAUAUCCAGACAGAUUUUUUUUGUUUCAAUAAGUAUUCUGAUUCCUUCCAUUAAGUUGAUAUAAUUGUUUAGCUAGUAUUUAUCGUUGAGUAACUGUUACAACCACAGUGUUGGAGCUGGGAGGUUAAACACAAAAGCAAGUAGCUGUCUUAUGAUAGAAUGUGUCUGAAAAAGCACAGUGGGAGCCAUCAAAAGAAGUUAACAGUUCUAUCUGGGAGAACAGAGGAGUCUUUAUCAGGAAUAUAACAUUUGAGAUGAAUUCCAGGUAUAGAAAGAUGGGUACAGCAUUGUACUCAUAGUAUGAACAGAGCCACUGAAGAAUAAGGUUAUAUAACAUGUAUAUCUAGCAGAGAUACACCUAGUUUUUAUUUUCUUUUGUUGGCAAAUCAUAUUUUGGAUUUGUAACACUACUUAUUUUUUUUGAAGUCCUUUGAAAUGUUUGGUCAAAAAUGAUUCUUAAGAGCUUAUUGCUUUAAACGAAAUAUUUUGGUAAGACUAUUCAUAAGACAUGAAGUGUCUGUAACUGAAUGGAUUCUGUUUUUCUGGUUCCUUGAAAGUGGUGACGUCUGUUGAUAGAAAAGGAACCUGGUAGUUAUAUGAUAUGUAAAAGAAAGACUAUUAACAAAAUAUGAAACAUUUGAUUGAUUUGUAUAUACUGGUGAUGUGUACUUUAUAUUUCACAUUAAACUUACAAUUUUGUUUUUCUUUUUGAGACGGAGUCUAGCUCUGUCACCCUGGCUAGAGUGCAGUGCAGUGGUACGAUCUCGGCUCACUGCAACCUCUGCCUCCUGGGUUUAAGCGAUUCUCCUGCCGCAGCCCCCUGAGUAGGUGGGAUUACAGGCACCUGCCACCACUCCCAGCUAAUUUUUUAAUUUUUAGUAGAGAUGGGGUUUCACCAUAUUGGCCAGGCUGGUCUCGAACUCCUGACCUCAUGAUCCGCCCGCCUCGACCUCCCAAAGUGCUGGGAUUACAAGUGUGAGCCACCGCGCCCGGCCCCCCAAAUUUUUUAAUGAAUAUAUAUUAAUUUAAAUUGCUAGUAGAUGAUCAGAAAAUAGAAAUUAUUUAACCACCAUAAUAUUUGUGAAUUUAAAAAAAUGUCAGUGAUAGCUAACGUAAGUUGGUAUUGCUUUUCUUUUCUGUCUUCCUGGAAUUAAGAGUUAUCAUUGUGUGGGAAUGGUAAUUGACAUCUUUUAACUUACUCUGAAAUGUUUUUGGGGGGAGUAAGGUACUUUUUACAGUCUACUCUACCAGCUGAGCUGUCAAAGUUUGCAUAUAAGUUACUUUUUUAAAAGUGCAUAGCUCCAUGACAUUUUACAUAUAAAUACACUGCGGUGACCACUAUCAAGAGCAAGAACAUAUCCAUAACCCCCAAAAGUUACUCAUGUACCUUUCUAGUCAUAAAUACCCUUACUACACCCCUGAGUAAUCAUUAUUCUGGCUUUUCUCUCCUUAGGUUAGUUUUGAUUGUUCUUGAAUUUUUUCUGUUUUGGAGAUGGAGUCUUGCCCUGUCACCGAGGCUGGAGUGCAGUGGCAUGAUCUCAGCUCACUGCAACCUCUGCCUCCUGGAUUAAAGCGAUUCUCCUGCAUCAGCCUCCCAAGUAGCUGGGAUUACAGGCACACGCCACCAAGCCUGCCUAAUUUUUGUAUUUUUAGUAGAGACAGGGUAUCCCCAUGUUGGCUAGGCUCGUCUCGAACUCCUGACCUCAGGUGAUCCCUCCCCUCCCUGGCCUCCCAAAGUGCUAGGAUUACAGACGUGAGCCACCACACCCAUCCUUGAAUUUAAUUUAAAUGCAUUUAUACAGUCACACAGCACGUGCUCAUUUGUAUCUCACUUCUUUCGUUCAUCUAUUUUGAGAGUGUAUCAGUAGCUUGUUUUUUGUUGUCUUUUUAAAAAAUUGUUUAGAGUAUUCCAUUAUAUGAAUAAAUUACACUUUAAAAAUAUAUUCGGCUAUUACAAAUGUUUGUUUUUUUCCAGUUUUAGCUAUUAUGAAUAAAACUGCUAUAAACAUUCUUGCACACAGCAGGAUUUGUACAUAUUAUACUUAUUUAGACAAUAUUUGUGUAUAUAUAUAUACACACCACUAAUUUCUAUAAAGUAUUUAUUCUGAACAUGGCUUCUUUGCCAGAUAUAUGCGUUGUGUUCUGAAAUUUUACAUAUAAUAUUACUUUGAGAUUUUUUUUUUGCUUAGCUUCUUCAAAGACUAGAGCAGGAAAGAGUGACUUGAUUUAUAGAGUGAAGAUCAAAAAAAUUAACCUGGCAAACAAAACUGAUUAAUGUCUUUGUCAUCAUCUUGCAUUAGUUGUCAAGCCUGUCUUGUAUGGGGUACAUGUGGGAAAUUUUCAAUAUACCAUUUUAACCCAAGGACAAAUGACCUUUCAGUAACAUAAAAUACAUAGUAUGCUUUUAAAGGUGUUUCUUAUUUCAAUAAGCAAUGGAGUUAGUUUCUUCUUCCCGUUUUGCUUUUUAAAGUGAAAAUUUUUUAGGUUUUUAAAUUUCAGUAGGGAUCCAGAAGGGAAAUAAUAGAACAAUAGUAAUAGCUACCUUUUUUAGCACUAAGUAUGUGUCAGAUACUGUGCAGCGCACUUGGAUGUGACAAUUCACAGUUCCACCAGCAAUGUAGUUGCAUAUAGUUGUACCAGCAAAGUACCUGCUGCCCCAUAUCCCAACCAGUAUUAGUUGUUAUAUUUAAUUUUUACUAUCAGUGGAUGUAAGUGAUGCCAGCAUAUCUUUUUUUUUUUUUUUUGAGACAGAGUCUUGCUCUGUCUGUCGCCCAGGCUGGAGUACAGUGGCACGAUCUCAGCUCACUGCAACCUCCGCCUCCCGGGUUCAAACGAUUCUCCUGCCUUAGCCUCCUGAGUAGCUGGGAUUACAGGCGCAUGCCACCGUGCCUGGCUAAUUUUUGUAUUUUUAGUAGAUACUAAGUUUCACCAUGUUGGUUAGGCUGGUCUCGAACUCCCGACCUCGUGAUCCUCCCACCUCGGCCUCCCAAAGUUCUGGGAUUACAGGCAUGAGCCACUGCAUGUGGCCUAGCAUAUCUUUAGUUUGCAAUUCUCUGGCUACCAGUAAAUUUGAAUGAUUUGCUCUUCUAUUUAUGUUCUUUGUACAUUUAUCUAUGAAGUCUUUUUAAGAUAACAGUUUCUAAACACUCUCCAUAUAUUAUGUUUACUGAUCCUUUUCAUAUGCAUUAUAAAUAUAUUUUUUAAUGAUUUUAUUUAUGGUUUUAUGCCAUACAAGACAUUUGCAGUUUUUAUGUAGAAAAUUGUGUCUUGGUUAAGACCUCUUCUGUCUCUAUAUUUUGUAAAUGUGGUUUCCAACAUUUUCUUGCAAGAUUUUUAUUCUGUGUGUUAAUUUUUAUGUCUUUAAUCCAUCUGGAAUUUAUUUUUGUAUGUGGCAUGAGAAAGCAGUUCGAUUUUACUUUCUUCCAGAUGGAUAACCAGUUGUGCUACUCCUAUUUUCCUACUCAGUAGAACUACCAUCUUUGUCAUAUUUUAAAUUCUCAUAUAUGCUGGGAUUGAUUUCUAGAUUGUUCUUUGUAUUAUUUGUUUGCAUAUUCCUGUCCCCACACUGUUUUGAUUAAAAAGGCUUUGUAUUAUUUCUGAUAGCUGUGAAAGCAAAUCUUUGUUUUCUAUCUCAUACCUUACUUGACUAUUCUGCAAAUUUAAUCUGCCAUAAAAACCUUAAAAUCUUUUAUCCAAUCUCACUACCACCAUCACCCUAUAAGGUUAUGUGGAGAUUGUUAUUUGAAUUGCAUUUAAUUUACAUACCAGUUGAAGGUAUAAGUUUAACAUGUGAGAAUGCAGUAUGUCUUUUUAUUUGUUCAGAUCUUUCUUUUCUUUUUUUUUUUUUUUUUGCCUUCAAGAAUUCUGAAUUGCCUUCAUAGGGAUCUUGUAGCUUUAUUGUUAAAUUGGUUCCUAAGAAUUAACUUAGCAUGUUCACACUACAGCAAAUGGAAUAGUUUUGUCAGUUUCCAUUUGUAGGUGCUAACUGCUACAAUAGGGAAAAAGAGAGUGAUUUUUACAUUUUUUCUAUUUGCCUCUUAAUAUUUUGAUUAAUUGUCCUAACUUUAUAUCGUCAUCUUUUGAGAUUUUCAGGUGUGUAAUAAUAUCAGCAGUAAAAACGGUUUUACCUCUUUUACAAUGUUUAUGCAGCCUACUACAUUUUCUUGGUUUCGUCUUUAUAUUUUAUAGAAGCAUUAAGACAAUGUUAAAUGAUGAUGGUGAUAACUAGCACCCCCAUCUAAUUCCUGAAUUUAAUUAAAAUGGUUUUAGUUUUUCAAUCUUUUGGAAAACAUAUUCUUUUUUUUUUUUUUUUUUGGUAAACAGUUUGUUUUUGGCCGGGCGCAGUGGCUCACGCCUGUAAUCCCAGCACUUUCGAAGACCGAGGCUGGUGGAUUACCUGAGGUCAGGAGUUUGAGACCAGCCUGGGGAACAUGGCAAAAUCCUGUCUCUACUAAAAAUACAAGAAUUAGCCGGCCGUGGUGGUGGGCACCUAUAAUCACAGCUACUCGGGAGCCUGAGGCAGGAGAAUCGCUUGAACCCCGGAGGCAGAGGUUGCAGUGAGCCAAAAUAGUGCCACUGCACUUCAGCCCAGGUGACAGAGUGAGACUUAAAAUAAUAAUAAAUUGUGUUUAAUUUAAGUGGUUUCCUUCUAUCCCUGCUUUGGAUUUUUUAUUAGGAAUGUUACUGAAUUUUAUCAGCUUUUUCAGGACUAUUACUGAUUUUCUUUAAUUUGUUAAUGGAAUAAGUUACAUAAUCUAUCAACAUGUGAUAGACUUCUUAUAUUGAACUACUACCCUUGGCUUCAUGGAAUAAAUUUUUAUAGACCAAGCA